GUCUUCCCCUCGUGGGCCCUGAGCGGGACUGCAGCCAGCCCCCUGGGGCGCCAGCUUUGGAGGCCCCCGACAGCUGCUCUCGGGAGCCGCCUCCCGACACCCGAGCCCCGCCGGCGCCUCCCGCUCCCGGCUCCCGGCUCCUGGCUCCCUCCGCCUCCCCCGCCCCUCGCCCCGCCGCCGAAGAGGCCCCGCUCCCGGGUCGGACGCCUGGGUCUGCCGGGAAGAGCGAUGAGAGUGCGGAGGAACUGAGCCCCGGGAGGAGGUGCUCCUGUGCAGCCCCACUGAGUCAGCUCAUCUAUCGCCUGCCCUCCACCUGGCCAGUCCCUGCGGGCAUCUAACUGCUAAGCCUCCGCUCAGCCAACACCCAGUUGGUCAGUCUGGUCACAGUCCAGCAAAAAGAGGGACUGCCACUCUAACCCACCAGUGACACCACUCUUCCCGGCUGGAUGGUCAAUUAGCUCUGGCAUGAGAGAAUGUCACUGCCGAGAUGCUGCCCCCACCCCCUUAGGCCCGAGGGAUCAGGAGCUAUGGGACCAGAGGCCCUGUCAUCUUUACUGCUGCUGCUCUUGGUGGCAAGUGGAGAUGCUGACAUGAAGGGACAUUUUGAUCCUGCCAAGUGCCGCUAUGCCCUGGGCAUGCAGGACCGGACCAUCCCAGACAGUGACAUCUCUGCUUCCAGCUCCUGGUCAGAUUCCACUGCCGCCCGCCACAGCAGGUUGGAGAGCAGUGACGGGGAUGGGGCCUGGUGCCCCGCAGGGUCGGUGUUUCCCAAGGAGGAGGAGUACUUGCAGGUGGAUCUACAACGACUGCACCUGGUGGCUCUGGUGGGCACCCAGGGACGGCAUGCCGGGGGCCUGGGCAAGGAGUUCUCCCGGAGCUACCGGCUGCGUUACUCCCGGGAUGGUCGCCGCUGGAUGGGCUGGAAGGACCGCUGGGGUCAGGAGGUGAUCUCAGGCAAUGAGGACCCUGAGGGAGUGGUGCUGAAGGACCUUGGGCCCCCCAUGGUUGCCCGACUGGUUCGCUUCUACCCCCGGGCUGACCGGGUCAUGAGCGUCUGUCUGCGGGUAGAGCUCUAUGGCUGCCUCUGGAGGGAUGGACUCCUGUCUUACACCGCCCCUGUGGGGCAGACAAUGUAUUUAUCUGAGGCCGUGUACCUCAACGACUCCACCUAUGACGGACAUACCGUGGGCGGACUGCAGUAUGGGGGUCUGGGCCAGCUGGCAGAUGGUGUGGUGGGGCUGGAUGACUUUAGGAAGAGUCAGGAGCUGCGGGUCUGGCCAGUCUAUGACUCAGUGAAUGGCAGCAGCCUCAGCCUCUCAAGUAGCUAUUUUGAGAUGGAGUUUCACUUUGCCCGGCUGAGUGC